CUUCCCGAGCUAUCCUGACCUUGGCUUUAAUAAUUCAUAAAUGCCACUAACGAUCUACAAGUGAAAAGCAUUUUCACAUCAAGGUCUAAUUGGACCCUCGUGGCCACCCGGAGACACAGGAACGACUAAAUACAUUCUGCAGAUGAGGAAACAAAGGCUCAUAGAGGGGAAGGGGUUUACGUUGCCUAAGAACUCUGACACUAGUAUAGACAGGCCCGCACUGACUCUGAGAUACAUCACGUACCAGCUGUGGUCCUUUGAGAAGAGGGCAGCCAAGAUGACCCGAUGGUCCAGUUACCUGUUGGGAUGGACAACCUUCCUUCUCUAUUCCUAUGAGUCAAGUGGAGGGAUGCAUGAGGAAUGUGUCUUUCCUUUCACCUACAAGGGAUCUGUUUACUUCACUUGCACCCAUAUUCAUAGCUUAUCCCCUUGGUGUGCCACCAGAGCCGUGUACAACGGCCAGUGGAAGUACUGCCAGAGUGAAGAUUACCCACGCUGUAUCUUCCCUUUCAUCUAUCGAGGAAAGGCUUAUAACAGCUGCAUCUCCCAGGGCAGCUUCUUAGGCAGUCUGUGGUGCUCAGUCACCUCUGUCUUCGAUGAGAAACAGCAGUGGAAAUUCUGUGAAACGAAUGAGUAUGGGGGAAAUUCUCUCAGGAAGCCCUGCAUCUUCCCCUCCAUCUACAGAAAUAAUGUGGUCUCUGAUUGCAUGGAGGAUGAAAGCAACAAGCUCUGGUGCCCAACCACAGAGAACAUGGAUAAGGAUGGAAAGUGGAGUUUCUGUGCCGACACCAGAAUUUCCGCGUUGGUCCCUGGCUUUCCUUGUCACUUUCCGUUCAACUAUAAAAACAAGAAUUAUUUUAACUGCACUAACGAAGGAUCAAAGGAGAACCUUGUGUGGUGUGCAACUUCUUACAACUACGACCAAGACCACACCUGGGUGUAUUGCUGAUGCUGAGGAAAGGAGAAAUAUCUUCAGAGGAAGACUGCCGCCAUACUGAGGCUGAGCACAGAUUUGUCUUUUUCAUUGCAUCUGUCAAGCUUAAAUAACCACCUUUAGAAAUACCCUCUGCACCACCUGCUUCAAUCAGCUGGUCCUUUGUGAAGAACGUAGAGAGAAUGCGGCAUAACCACCAAUAAAGGAGUCUUGAUUUAACCCUGG